AAUUCAGGUCCAACUCAUAAGGGAAAUGCUUUCUGAGAGUCAUGGACCUCCUGUGCAAGAACAUGAAGCACCUGUGGUUUUUCCUCCUGCUGGUGGCAGCUCCCAGAUGGGUCCUGUCCCAGGUGCAGCUGCAGGAGUCGGGCCCAGGACUGGUGAAGCCUUCGGAGACCCUGUCCCUCACCUGCACUGUCUCUGGUUACUCCAUCAGCAGUGGUUACUACUGGGGCUGGAUCCGGCAGCCCCCAGGGAAGGGGCUGGAGUGGAUUGGGAGUAUCUAUCAUAGUGGGAGCACCUACUACAACCCGUCCCUCAAGAGUCGAGUCACCAUAUCAGUAGACACGUCCAAGAACCAGUUCUCCCUGAAGCUGAGCUCUGUGACCGCCGCAGACACGGCCGUGUAUUACUGUGCGAGAGACACAGUGAGGGGAGGUGAGUGUGAGCCCAGACACAAACCUCCCUGCAGGGAGGCUGAGGGGACCGGCGCAGGUGCAGCUCACGGCCAGCAGGGGGCGCGCGGAGCUCACGGAAUACAAGGCCGGGUCAGGAGCAGGUGCAGGGUGAGCGGGGCUUGCUCAUCUUCUCAGAGAUCAUCAUCUCCCUCCUCGCCAGCACCUCAGCUUUCCGUAGAGGUCCUCUUUCUUUAUUGUCUGUGGUUCUACUUCCUCACAUCCUUGUGCCAGGAAAGAAAGGAGUAAGGCAAAUUUUCCUGUUACAAUUGAAGUUUCACCAAUUACUAAAAACUUUCCUGCAAGUACCUGCACAGCCCAUUAUACCUUAUUUAUAUAUAUAUAUUCUAAUGCUUCUCACCAUCUCUUGAUUUGUGUCAUCAAUUUAAUUGUGCCCUUUUUGAAAUUCAUAUGCUGAAACUUUAAAUCCAAUGGAUCUAUAUCGGAAUUUUAAUGGUAUAAUUAACGUUAAAUGUGGUCAUAAGUGAGACCCUAAUGCAAUAGACCUGUUGUCUUUAUAAGAAGAGGAAGAGACACCAGAGACCUCUCACUUCUCACAUGCACACAGAGAAGAGGCCACGUGGAGACAUAGUGCACUAGAAGGUGGGCCUCUGCAAGCCAGGAAGAAGCCGCACCAAGAACCAACCCUGCCAGCACCUUGAUCUUCUACAUUCAGACUGCAGAAUUGUAAGAAAAUCAAUAUUUGUUGUUUAAGCCACCCACUCCUUUUGUCUUCUUACGAAGACCCAGACAGGCUAAUACCACACAACUCUGUUAGCUCCAUCUCCUGGAGGGAGAAGCAGCCCCCUGAGGCUGGGCACAUCGCUCAGAUUUUCACAUGAAUUAGGCAAAAACAGUAGCUCUCAUAUAAAAACUGUCACGUCCCUGUUGGGACAAGGUCUUUUAAACAAACCCUGGGGCUUUGUCACAAAUGUUGCAUUUUAUCCUUUAUUAGGACUUAACUAAUUGACAAUGAGUACCAGCUGGAUGGAAACUGACCACUGACCAUCUUCUGCUGUCUCCUUAUUAUAUCACAGAAAACCACAGCAACAUUACUCUAUGUCUUCAACUUUCUAAAUUUGUACUGAAUCUAUUGCUAAAUGAGGAGCUACAUGGGGUCUGAGUUUUGUUAUCUUCUUCCCAGUCUUCCCCAAUUACCAAGCACAGAAGAUACUUUCAGUGAAAUUUAGCUGUCAAUGCCCCCAACACCACAUCAUGUUUUAAGGUCCAAGGACUUUCUUUGGGGGGCUAUUGAAAACACUUUUGAAUGGAAAAUCCUAAAGCAUACAACAGCUGAAAGAAUGGCCCCUGUGCACGUGAAGGCUGAAGGGAUGGAUGAUAGGGUACGUUCCUCCAAGGUGUUCCUGGGCAUGUGAUGGUUGGAUACCUCAUGCAUACGAAAACAAGGACUGAACUGAGAUAGAAACAAGGGCCAUAUCCUAUAGGAAAACAAGAAAAAAACGGGCAUCCCUGAAGAGAGUUAAUUAGACUUGGUGGGUUUAAGAUGAAUUUUUUUCCAAAGUUUUUUAAUGUUCUAAGCUAAAUAUGAAUAUUUUCAAUAAACUGCAAAUUAAAAGGA